ACGCUGGGGCUUCAGGUCUCCUAGCAACAAGUUGUACCAUAUGAGGACGGCCGCUGAGGUGAGUACUUAGAGAGGGUCAAAUUCAGAAUUUGCAGGUGCAACCCGGAAAGUCCCCGCGGACCUAGAGGCCCUGCUUUUCAAUUAGCCUGACCCUAUGCACAGAGAGGUCCCUGCGGGACAGGGUCGCUUCACAGAGGCAGCUGGCCGAGGCCGCUCACCCGCCGCUGUAAUGGUGUGUGGUUGCCCACCAGCCACCGUCCCCUCGAGCCCCCACCACCCGCUCUACCGCCCCCUCGAGCCCCCACCACCCGCCCCACCGCCCUCUGCUGCCUGGGGCUGUUGCUGGUUCCAGGCCUUCGGGUCGCCCCUUGGCCUCUGGUUAUGUGAGCCCAUAGUCCUUCCUGCCUUGGUGACAUCGUAUACGAAAAGCCGGGGCUCGAUUUGGACAUAGUAGGAAUCCUAUUAUUGAGACCCUGUAUAUAGAAAAACAUGGCAGUUUCUACCUUCAUCAGUUAAUAAAAUCAACCAUAAUGGAGAUAUCAAUGCCUCCACCUCAGAUAUAUGUAGAAAAAACUCUGGCCAUUAUCAAACCAGAUAUUGUUGACAAAGAGGAGGAGAUACAAGAUAUUAUUCUUAGAUCCGGAUUCACCAUUGUUCAGAGAAGAAAACUACGCCUCAGCCCUGAGCAAUGUAGUAACUUUUAUGUGGAAAAGUAUGGAAAAAUGUUUUUCCCCAACUUAACAGCUUACAUGAGUUCUGGACCACUUGUCGCCAUGAUAUUAGCUAGACAUAAAGCCAUCUCUUAUUGGUUAGAACUUUUGGGACCAAAUAAUAGCUUAGUAGCGAAGGAGACACAUCCAGACAGUCUGAGGGCAAUUUAUGGCACAGAUGACCUAAGGAAUGCACUUCAUGGGAGUAAUGACUUUGCUGCUGCGGAAAGAGAAAUACGUUUUAUGUUUCCUGAAGUGAUUGUUGAGCCCAUUCCAAUUGGACAAGCUGCUAAGGACUAUUUAAAUUUACAUAUAAUGCCAACUCUGCUUGAAGGACUCACAGAGCUUUGUAAGCAAAAACCAGCAGAUCCUUUGUUUUGGUAUAUGUGCUGCCGAAGAGAGCACUGGACUCUCAGGUCCAUUCUAUUGGUCUGCAUGUCUGGCAUAAGGAUGUCAUUACCACACUGUGCUGACUACUGUAGCUUUGUAGAAGGUUUUGAAAUUGAGAGUACAAAUCAGUCCUCCAACUUUGUUCUUUUUCAUGAUUGUUUUGGCUCCUCAGAGCCCCUUGCAAUUUCAUAUGAAUUUGAGGAUUGGCUUUCCAUUUCUGCAAAAAAACUUGUUGGACAUUUGGCAAGAGCUGCACUGAAUCUGUAGAUUGCUUUGGGAAGUAUUGACAUCUUAACAAUAUCAAAUCUCCGUAUCCAUGAAAAAUAAUGUCUUCUCAUUUAUUUAGGUAUUCUUUAAUUUCUUUCAGCAAUGUUCUACAGUUCUUAAUGUAUAAGCCUUUCGCUUCUUGGGUUAAAUUUAUCCCUUGGCAUUUUAUUUGUCUUUAUGCUACUGUAAAUGAAAGUGAUUUAAAAUUUUUUUUUGGACUGUCAUUGCUGAUGUAUAGAAAUACAGUUGAUUUUUGUGUAUUGUAACCUACAUCUUCGCUGAAUUUAUUAGCUGUAGUGGCUUCCUUGUAAAUUCCUUAGGGUUUUCCACAUGUAGGUUUAUGCCAUCUGUGAAAAGAGAUAGUUUUACUUCUUUCUUGCCAGUUUGGAUCUAUUCUUGACAAUCUUGCAUAAUGUAAAUCCAAAUGUUUCCAUUUUUAAUGGUCAUUUUCUUAAAGUGAUUUUGAAAACUGUUUAAGUUUCCAAUUGAUAUAGUAUAUAUUGAAAGGAAAUAUGUAACUGUUUCUUAACUUAGGUUGUUUUUUUUUUUCCCAUAGAUUUGGCUAGCUGAUUGGCUGCUGAAAAAUAAUCCUAACAAACCCAAACUUUGUCACCAUCCAAUUGUAGAAGAACCUUAUUAAAAAAAAAAUCCUCGAAAGAACAAAUCAUGAACUAUCUUAUUAUAAAAGGCUGUACUUCUACUGUUUGAAAAAAUUAUUUCUAGGGUUUAAGUAACUACAAGUAAAAUAAAUUUAUUUCUUAAAAAUAA